GUCAGCAGCGAGAGGGUUCGAAGAUGGCGGCGCGCAAGGGUCGGCGGCGCACGUGUGAAACCGGGGAACCCAUGGAAGCCGAGUCCGGCGACACAAGUUCCGAGGGCCCGGCCCAGGUCUACCUGCCCGGCCGGGGGCCGCCGCUACGCGAAGGGGAGGAGCUGGUCAUGGACGAGGAGGCCUAUGUGCUCUACCACCGAGCGCAGACUGGCGCCCCCUGUCUCAGCUUUGACAUAGUCCGGGAUCACCUGGGAGACAACCGGACAGAGCUUCCUCUUACACUUUACUUGUGUGCUGGGACCCAGGCUGAGAGCGCCCAGAGCAACAGACUGAUGAUGCUUCGGAUGCACAAUCUGCAUGGGACAAAGCCCCCACCCUCAGAGGGCAGUGAUGAAGAAGAAGAGGAGGAAGAUGAAGAGGAUGAAGAAGAGCGGAAACCUCAGCUGGAGCUGGCCAUGGUGCCCCACUAUGGUGGCAUCAACCGAGUUCGGGUGUCAUGGCUGGGUGAAGAGCCUGUGGCUGGGGUGUGGUCAGAGAAGGGCCAGGUGGAGGUGUUUGCGCUGCGGCGGCUUCUGCAGGUGGUGGAGGAGCCCCAGGCCCUGGCAGCCUUCCUCCGGGAUGAGCAGGCCCAAAUGAAGCCCAUCUUCUCCUUCGCUGGACACAUGGGCGAGGGCUUUGCCCUUGACUGGUCCCCCCGGGUGACCGGUCGCCUGCUGACCGGUGACUGUCAAAAGAACAUCCACCUCUGGACACCUACGGACGGCGGCUCCUGGCACGUGGACCAGCGGCCAUUCGUGGGCCACACACGCUCUGUGGAGGACCUGCAGUGGUCACCGACUGAGAACACGGUGUUUGCCUCCUGCUCAGCUGACGCCUCCAUCCGCAUCUGGGACAUCCGGGCAGCCCCCAGCAAGGCCUGCAUGCUCACCACAGCCACCGCCCAUGAUGGGGACGUCAAUGUCAUCAGCUGGAGCCGCCGGGAGCCCUUCCUGCUCAGUGGCGGGGAUGAUGGGGCCCUCAAGAUCUGGGACCUUCGGCAGUUCAAGUCUGGUUCCCCAGUGGCCACCUUCAAGCAGCACGUGGCCCCCGUGACCUCCGUCGAGUGGCACCCCCAGGACAGCGGGGUCUUUGCAGCCUCGGGUGCAGACCACCAGAUCACACAGUGGGACCUGGCAGUGGAGCGGGACCCUGAGGCGGGCGACGUGGAGGCCGACCCCGGACUGGCCGACCUCCCGCAGCAGCUGCUGUUCGUGCACCAGGGCGAGACCGAGCUGAAGGAGCUGCACUGGCACCCGCAGUGCCCAGGGCUCCUGGUCAGCACGGCGCUGUCAGGCUUCACCAUCUUCCGCACCAUCAGCGUCUGAGGCGUCCCACUGGCUCUGAUCUUGCUUCCUGCUUGGAAACUGAAGUCGAAUUGGGCUCCCCUGGAAGGGGUUCAUUCAGGUCUGUUGACUGAGACUGGCCGGCCUGUGGGCUGCCGUGAUGGAUUCUGUUUGACGUAUUGUUCUCUAGAAGGCCUGGCUCUGAUCCAGUGACCCCUCUCACCAAAGAACUCGGUUUAACCAGGGCUCUGUAAGACCACUCCCACCCAGAGACUUGUGUGGCCUGGUGUGGCCUGUGUGUCGGAUUCCUUCCUGUCAGCUGUGACCCAUUUGACCUGUGUCCCCAGAACCCAGUUUUUUGUUUGUUUGUUUGAGACGGAGUCUUGGUCUGUCGCCCAGGCUGGAGUGCAGUAGCACGAUCUUGGCUCACUGCAACCUCCGCCUCCUGGGUUAAAGUGAUUCUCUCAGCUCAGUCUCCCAGGUAGCUGGGAUUACAGGCAUGUGCCACCACACCCCGUUAAUUUUUGUAUUUUUAGUAGAGACGGGGUUUCACCAUGUUGGCCAGGCUGGUCUCAAAUUCUUGAUCUCAAGUGAUCUGUCCGCCCCGGCCUCCCAGAGUGCUGGGUUGGGAUUACAGGCGUGAGCCACCGCGUCCGGCUCAGGACCCAGUUUUGGCUGCUGGUUCCCAGCAGGGGACUCGGGGGAUAUACAGUGGCUGCACCAAAUUGGAGGUGUGGGUUCCUCCAACACAAUUUGCUUCUGCCCGUUGUCUUCCUGCCAGCUGGGUUUGGCCAGGAUUUCUCCGUGUGGGGGCUACAUGCGACCCUCUCCCCUCCUCCCUGACUUUAGAGGCUGGUGCUGUGUCGGGAGGAAGGUCAGGGCUCCUGAGCAGCAAUAAAGGACCAGGAAGAGGCCUGAGGUGUAUUUGAGACUCUGGUCCUUUGGCCACAGCCCUAUGAGGAAACGGGGUGUGGGGGGAGUUUGGGGGUGGGGAGGAAUUUGGCACCAGCUGCCCCCAGGCCGCUAGGCUGGGGGAGGCCACUGGGAGUCCAGUGCAACCCAACCUUCCGCCCACUGGGUGCCGCCGCGUUCUGCCUUCUCUAAGUGUCCUUCCAUCUGGAACUCACUCUGGCUUAGUGAAAGGGGCCUCAUCCCUGACCCCCACCAGCUUAUGAAGGCUUCAUCUCAGGGAACUCUGGACCCCCCAUUUCUCCCUCCGUCCAUCUCCCCUUUAUCACGUUUCUUUCUUUCUUCUCUGUGUCCCCCUCUUUCAGAGUCUCCCGUCCCCCACUGCCAGUCUCCCUGCCCCCUAGUCGCUGUCUCGCUCCUCCGCCGCUGUCUCCUGUCCAGCCUGCCUGGGCUGUGGCCCAGCCGCUCUGCCUGGCUGGCCUCCCUGGCUCCCCCUCUGCGGCUCUGAGCUAGCCCCACCCCCGGCCCCCCUCCAUCCAGCCUCUGAUCCAUCUGUGGACUCCGAGGUCGGGUGCCCGUCACACGGCCCCUGGGACCAAGGACAGACUACAGCCCCUCAGCACCCACAGAGGCUUCCCCUCAGCCCUAGCCGAGGAGCCCCCAGCGGAGGGCAUGGGGGUGGGCCGCCCCAACAGGUACGUGCCUCCAUGCAAGGCACCGCUGAGCCAUCCCCUCCUGCUCUGCUGCGUCGCCCCCAUCCACCCCUGCCCCAGCAUCCCUGUCCUCAGCUUGUCCCCUUCAAGAAGGCCUUGUCUUCCCAUCAGUGACAGGCUCAGCGCCAGGAGAAUCCACCCCCAGGUUCAGUGCCUCCAACUCUCACCCCAUCCCCAUUUUAUGCAUUUUCUCACUGGCUUCCAUCCUUUCAGAGAAACCCUCUCAGUCUGUCUGUCUCUGUCUCUGUCUCUCUCCCCCAUCUCUGUCUCUCCCAUCUCUCUCUGCCUCUCUCUGUCUUCACAAUUUCAUCUCCCCAUGUCGCCAUUUCUUAAAACAUUUCUUUUCUCCUUUUCGUUUUCCCAAUUGCCCUGUCCGCCUCUAUCUUCUCUGUCCCCCUCCAUCUAGGUCUCUGUCCCCCCCUCUCUCUGGGUCUCUGUCCCCCUCUGUCUCUGAGUCUCUAUCCUCUCAAGGUCUCUGUUCCCCUCUCUCUGGGUCUCUGUCCUCUCUCAAGGUCUCUGUCCCUUUCUCUCUGGAUCAAUGUCCCUUUCCUGCUGCCCUCUCUGGGUCUCUGUCCCCCUCUCUCUCAGGGUCCCUGUCCUGCUUGGUCCCUGUACUUUUUCUUGGGGCACCCUCUCAACACCCCUCCUCCUGCCUAUCUCUGCAUCUCUUUGUCUUUCUGUAGUCUCUGCUUUCCAACCUGCUGUCCAGCCCCCACCAGUAGGUGGGGAGUGGUGGGGAACACCCCUGGUUUCGGAAGAGUGAGAGUGUUGAUUUGGGAGGGUGAGGGUGGGGCCUGGGGGCGGGGCUUCUUGGCCUCAGAUUAGACAGUGACUUUGACACGAAGUUGAAGCACCUUAAGCCCUGUAUCUCCUUUAUAUGGAAACAUUAAGCUGCUCUCGCAGGUCAGGUGGAGGAUCCCUUUCCCUCCCGCCCUGCUUUUGCUAGGGGAGGGGGGUGCCCUGAGCCUGAGUCGCAGCCAGCCUGGGAGCUGGGCCAUGUUGGCCGCAGAUGGCCCCCUGGUGAAGGUUCCCGUUGGCUUUGGGAAGUAGACAACGGGUCUGCCUCACGGGGCUGAGGUGGGACUGGAGGAUUUCGAGGGCAGAACUCUGGGAAGGAAAGAAAGGCUUAGGACCCAACCAGCAUUCCCCCUGGCACUGCGGGGGCCUGGCCAGCUCAUGGCGUUCCCUGAGCCUGUUCCCCAACUGUGAAAGGGGGUGAUGAUCUUCACCUCCCGGCAUCCUGAGCGGCCAAGGUGAGCAGUGGGGUCUGAGAGUCCAGUGGGGGCUGUGGGCAUGUCGGGAGCUCAUCACGAGGCCUCGUACAUACCAGGUGUGUUUGAAACCAGAGUGCUCUUGAGAAGACUGUGGUUUGUCACUCGGGCCGUGGCUCCCAGGAGGCCUGGGUGGGAGGCUAGCUUUUGCCACUCCUCUCCCCACUGGCUGAGAGACCUGCGACAAGGGACUAACCUCAGCCCCAGUUGGCUUUUCUGUGAAAAGCCAGGUCCCUUCAUCAAAGGGCUUUGGUGAGAGAUGGGCAAGUGGGGGUGAGAGGCCCAGGCUGGGGCCUGGGGAGCACAGGUCAGUGUCAGUGCCCACCUGCCCCCCCAGCCCACGGGGGUGGUUCCUGAGGGUGGAGUCAGUGCUGAGUGGGGAUCCCCAGGCUGGGGAGGGCUGCAGGUGUAGAUGCUGCAUCCUGAUGUUGACCUCCAGGCCGCCCCCUUGGGCAACGAGCCUAUUUCCCCUUUUUGGGAGAACAGUCUCUAACAUGCAGGGUUGUCAGGGGUGAGAUAGAGUCAAGGUUGGGGUACACUGUGGGCACUGGACACAGCCAGGCUGGUCCCCUCACCUCAGCCUUGCCUCUGUCAAGUGGGCCUAAUGAACCCUCGCGAAUGGCCAGGCUGCCUGCGUGGUUGUGGGAAGCAGGUGCAGGGCUUUGGGAGACCCAGUUGGUGCCAAACUUGACAUUGUCUCAUGGUCUUCUUUCCAAAUGGAGUGUGCCAGGCCCUGCCAAGAAGCCCCUGAGGAUCCCCAGGUUCCAGCACAAAUUAUUUAACCCCUGGAAUGGUUUGUCCUGAUCCAGCCAGUUCCUGGGAAGUUCCCCACCACAGGGCCAAGCGUUUGGUAACGUUGCAGUGAACCCUGAAGGCAAUGAGGGGUGCGGGUCCAUGCCCAGCCCUUUCCUUUGGUCCACCCUGACAGGCUGCUGCGAUUCCCUCCAUUUCUUUUCUUCCUUUAUUUUUUAUUUUUAAUUAUUUAUUUAUUUUUUAGAGACAGGGUUUUGCUGUCUUCCCCAGGCUGGUUCUCAAACCCCUGGCCUCACGCAUUCCUCCUGAGUUGGACUCCCAAAGUGCUAGGAUUACAGGUGUGAGCCACCGCACCUGCCCUCUUUUUUUUUUUUUUUUCUUUAAGAGAUAGGG